AGACCCGGAAGCGGAUCGCGGGGAGUGAAGGCUGCGCCGCCGAGCCUGAGUUUCGCUCUCUCUAGAUUAAAUCUGCGCUUCGCAGUCCCCCUUCUUCCAUCCCCCGGGUCUGGAGGGGUCCCUACAGAUCUUAAAAUGACCACACCGCGCCCUCCACCCCAGGGAAGGUUGACAUUCAGGGACGUGGCCAUCGAAUUCUCUCAGGAGGAGUGGAAAUGCCUGGACCCUGCUCAGAGGGCUUUGUACAGGGACGUGAUGUUGGAGAACUACAGGAACCUGGUCUCCCUGGCAGGAAUCUCUCUUUCUGAAAUGAGUAUUACCUCCAUGUUGGGGCAAGGGAAAGAGCCCUGGACUGUGGAGAGUGAAGUGAAAAUAACAAAAACAUCAAGUGGUUGGGAAUGCAUCAAAGGUGUGAACACAGGCUGCACCCACUAUCCAACCAAUUCCAGUGAGAUGAAGUGGGUACCUCAGUUGGAAAUGCAGAAAUCACCUGCCUUCUGUGUCGAUCUCGCUGGGAGCCGCAGGCCAGAGCUGUUCCUAUUUGGCCAUCUUGCCAGCAAAUCCCUAAUUUUUGCAUUUUUAAUGGAGAUGAGGUUUCACCAUUAA